AGGCACUGGGACCUAGAGCUCAGAAGACCGAGAGGACAGACUGCCGUGUUGCCACCACAGGCUGGACCAUGGACCCCCAAGAGAUGGUCGUCAAGAACCCAUAUGCCCACAUCAGCAUCCCCCGGGCUCACCUGCGGCCUGACCUGGGGCAGCAGUUAGAGGUGGCUUCCACCUGUUCCUCAUCCUCGGAGAUGCAGCCCCUGCCAGUGGGGCCCUGUGCCCCAGAGCCAACCCACCUCUUGCAGCCGACCGAGGUCCCAGGGCCCAAGGGCGCCAAGGGUAACCAGGGGGCUGCCCCCAUCCAGAACCAGCAGGCCUGGCAGCAGCCUGGCAACCCCUACAGCAGCAGUCAGCGCCAGGCCGGACUGACCUACGCUGGCCCUCCGCCCGCGGGGCGCGGGGAUGACAUCGCCCACCACUGCUGCUGCUGCCCCUGCUGCCACUGCUGCCACUGCCCCCCCUUCUGCCGCUGCCACAGCUGCUGCUGCUGUGUCAUCUCCUAGCCCAGCCCACCCUGCCAGGGCCAGGACCCAGACUUCAGCAAAUGUGGCUCACACAGUGCCGGGACAUGCCGGGACAUGCGGGGUGGCUGUUGUCAUGGGCGUCUGCCCCUUCACACCAGGCACUGGGGCUCAGACCCACCAGGAAGGUGGCCGUUCAGCCCGAGCUCCUGAAACGGAAUCCCAGGUCCUGGCUGGAGAGGGACACCCCUGAUUACCUUAAGGCCCAGGCAAUAAAGCAGGGUGAUCUUCCUCCCAGCAA